GGGUUCGCUCGCCGGCUCCGACGCAGACAUGGUGGACUGAUCCGCAGCGGGGCCGCGAACAGCGUUUCCUGAGGCACCUCCCGCGCGUGGUUCCGCCGCGCCCCGCGCCCUGCGCCCCUCAGCCCCUCGCCGGCGCCCGCGUCGCGGGUUGGCAGCCUAGCCCGGCAGCCGCGUUCCCGCCGCGUCCCGCGCCCGGUACCUAUGGAGGCGCCGCUCGCCGGCGAGGCCGCCGACCAUGCCUAGGAGGGCCGGGAGCGGUCAGCUGCCGCUGCCCCGGGGCUGGGAGGAGGCCAGGGACUACGACGGCAAGGUCUUCUACAUUGACCACAACACCAGGAGGACCAGCUGGAUCGACCCCCGGGACAGGUUAACGAAGCCCUUGUCAUUUGCUGAUUGUGUUGGGGAUGAGCUGCCGUGGGGAUGGGAAGCAGGGUUUGACCCUCAGAUUGGUGUCUACUACAUCGAUCACAUCAACAAAACCACGCAGAUAGAAGAUCCAAGAAAACAAUGGAGGGGGGAACAGGAGAAGAUGCUCAAGGACUACCUCUCUGUGGCACAGGAUGCCCUCCGGACACAGAAGGAACUGUACCAUGUGAAGGAGCAGAGGCUGGCGCUGGCCCUGGAUGAAUACGUGCGAUUAAAUGAUGCCUAUAAGGAAAAGUCAAGUUCUCACACAAGCUUAUUCUCAGGAUCUUCAUCCAGUACUAAAUAUGAUCCCGAUAUUUUAAAAGCUGAGAUCUCCACUACAAGAUUAAGGGUUAAAAAGCUAAAGAGAGAGCUCUCACAGAUGAAGCAGGAACUGCUCUAUAAAGAACAAGGCUUUGAAACAUUGCAGCAAAUUGAUAAAAAAAUGUCUGGAGGCCAGAGCGGGUAUGAACUCAGUGAAGCCAAAGCCAUUCUAACAGAACUAAAAUCUAUCAGAAAGGCAAUUAGCUCAGGAGAAAAAGAAAAACAAGAUCUGAUGCAGAGUCUUGCUAAGCUGCAGGAGCGGUUUCAUUUGGAUCAGAACAUUGGCAGAUCUGAGCCAGAUUUGAGAUGUAGUCCUGUGAACUCUCAUUUAUGUCUCUCCAGACAGACCCUUGAUGCUGGGUCACAAACAAGCAUUUCCGGAGAUAUUGGAGUAAGAAGUAGAUCAAAUUUAGCUGAAAAGGUCAGGCUAAGCCUACAGUAUGAAGAAGCCAAAAGAAGUAUGGCCAACUUAAAAAUUGAACUGUCAAAAUUGGACAGUGAGGCCUGGCCUGGGGCACUGGAUAUUGAGAAGGAAAAACUGAUGCUGAUUAAUGAAAAAGAAGAACUUUUGAAAGAGCUUCAGUUCGUCACCCCACAGAAACGUACCCAAGAUGAAUUAGAACGCCUAGAAGCUGAAAGGCAGCGGCUGGAAGAAGAGUUGCUGUCUGUGAGGGGAACACCAAGCAGAGCUCUGGCCGAGAGAUUGAGAUUGGAAGAGAGAAGAAAAGAGCUGCUACAGAAACUUGAAGAAACUACUAAAUUAACUACUUAUUUGCAUUCACAACUUAAAAGCCUCUCUGCCAGCACCCUGUCCAUGUCAUCUGGGAGCAGCCUGGGUUCCCUGGCAUCGAGUCGGGGCUCUCUGAACACCUCCAGCAGAGGGUCACUCAACUCCCUCAGUUCCACCGAACUCUAUUACAGCAGUCAAAGUGAUCAGAUAGAUGUGGAUUAUCAGUAUAAACUGGACUUCCUUCUGCAAGAGAAAAGCGGUUACAUUCCUUCUGGACCCAUCACCACCAUCCAUGAAAACGAGGUGGUCAAGUCCCCUAGCCAGCCUGGCCAGAGUGGACUCUGUGGAGUGGCAGCUGCAGCAACAGGCCACACUCCUCCACUGGCUGAGGCCCCGAAGUCUGUGGCCUCCCUGUCCUCGAGGUCCUCCCUUUCCUCCUUGUCUCCUCCAGGCUCUCCCUUGGUUUUGGAAGGCACGUUUCCCAUGUCUUCUUCUCAUGAUGCCUCUCUCCAUCAGUUCACUGCUGACUUUGAAGACUGUGAGUUGAGUAGCCAUUUUGCAGAUAUCAGCCUCAUCGAAAAUCAGAUUUUGCUGGAUUCUGAUUCAGGAGGAGCCUCCCAGUCUCUUUCAGAGGAUAAAGACCUUAAUGAAUGUGCUAGGGAGCCAUUAUAUGAAGGAACUGCAGAUGUGGAAAAAUCAUUACCAAAAAGAAGAGUGAUCCACUUGCUUGGGGAGAAAACCACUUGUGUGUCGGCUGCUGUGUCUGAUGAGUCUGUGGCUGGAGACAGUGGGGUCUAUGAAGCUUUCGUGAAACAACCUAGUGAAAUGGAAGAUGUCACAUACAGUGAAGAGGAUGUAGCCAUUGUAGAGACCGCCCAGGUUCAGAUAGGACUCAGAUACAAUGCAAAAAGUUCAAGUUUCAUGGUGAUUAUAGCACAGCUCCGAAACCUUCAUGCCUUCUUGAUACCUCAUACUUCAAAAGUAUAUUUUAGGGUUGCCGUUCUUCCUUCCUCAACUGAUGUCAGCUGUCUGUUUCGCACAAAAGUUCAUCCGCCCACAGAAUCCAUUUUAUUCAAUGAUGUGUUCAGAGUCGCCAUUUCCCAAACAGCCUUACAACAGAAGACACUGAGGGUAGACCUUUGCUCUGUCAGUAAACACCGAAGGGAAGAAUGCCUGGCUGGAACUCAGAUCAGCCUGGCAGAUUUACCAUUUUCCAGUGAGGUUUUCACUCUAUGGUAUAACUUGCUUCCUUCCAAGCAAAUGCCUUGCAAAAAGAAUGAAGAAAAUGAGGACUCUGUAUUUCAACCAAACCAGCCGUUAGUAGAUUCUAUAGACUUGGAUGCAGUGUCAGCCUUACUUGCAAGAACAUCAGCUGAGUUGUUAGCUGUGGAACAAGAAUUAGCACAAGAAGAAGAAGAAGAAUCAGGACAAGAAGAGCCAAGGGGCCCAGAUGGAGACUGGUUAAACACUUAUUUCCUUUGCUGUUGGGAGCUCAAAGAUGAUGUGUUUACACGGCUUACAGUGAAACCUUUGCUAACAAUGCUAAGAGAGGCCUCUGAUGAAAUUGUGGCUGAAAAAGAGGCUGAAGUUAAAUUGCCAGAGGACAGUAGCUGUACAGAAGAUUUAAGUUCAUGCACUAGUGUGCCUGAGAUGAAUGAAGACGGGAACAGGAAAGAAAGCAACUGUGCCAAAGACCUCAGAAGUCAGCCACCUACUAGAAUACCAACACUGGUUGACAAAGAGACAAACACUGAUGAAGCCGCUAAUGACAAUAUGGCAGUUCGCCCCAAAGAGCGCAGCAGCCUGAGCUCUAGACAGCAUCCGUUUGUGAGGAGCAGUGUGAUAGUGCGCUCACAGACCUUUUCUCCAGGAGAGCGGAACCAGUACAUCUGCAGGUUAAAUCGGAGUGACAGUGACAGUUCAACCCUGGCUAAAAAAUCACUGUUUGUGAGAAACUCCACCGAACGCCGCAGUUUGAGGGUCAAAAGGACGGUUUGCCAGUCAGUCCUUAGAAGAACAACACAGGAAUGCCCAGUGCGGACAUCUCUAGACUUAGAACUGGACCUUCAGGCAUCUCUGACCCGGCAGAGCCGCCUCAAUGAUGAGCUGCAGGCGCUGAGGGACUUGCGGCAGAAGCUGGAGGAACUGAAAGCUCAGGGAGAGACUGACCUUCCACCAGGCGUGCUGGAGGAUGAGAGGUUCCAGAGGCUUCUGAAGCAAGCUGAGAAGCAGGCUGAACAGUCCAAAGAAGAGCAGAAGCAAGGUCUGAAUGCAGAGAAGUUGAUGAGGCAAGUCUCCAAGGACGUGUGUCGGCUCCGGGAGCAGAGCCAGAAGGUGCCUCGGCAGGUGCAGUCCUUCAGGGAGAAGAUUGCCUACUUCACCAGAGCAAAGAUAAGCAUCCCAUCCCUGCCAGCUGAUGAUGUGUGAUUACAUGACUUAAGAAAUUAUUUUUUCAUCUGUUCACUUUCUUAGGGAGGGUAAAAGACUGAAGAUUUGUGUUUUUGUUUUGGUGUUUGGUUUUUUUUGGUAACGUAACUGUCAACUCUUGAAGAACUUUUAUUUCACAUCAGAUUUUCAACACAUUAAUUUGUAAAGUACCUUGAGUGUAAUUUUUAUAUGCUUAAAAAAGAAAAAAUCAUAUAAGAAAGAUGGGAUAACCUGGUACACAAAUGUUGCCCAGUAUGUGCGCAUUGCCAGUGGACUUCAUUUUGUAAAAAUGGAAUAGAGGCAGUACCCCACAUGUGUACUGUUGAGCCGGCUGUUGAGAAACAACUUGGUUCAGCCGGUGGUUUUGCUUCUCCUUUGUGUUCCUGUGAGUAGGCUGUGCCGAUGGCAGCAGCGCCACGUGGUAUCUGUGCGCUGGCGAGGAGAGGAGCGCUUUCCAUUUGGAGGCAGUGUGAGCACACGCUGGAGUGCAGCGUUCCAAAGUCCGCCCGAAAUGGAUGCUGCGUCCACGGCCAUCACCUGUGCGGGAACACCUGGUUUCCUUAAGACAAUUUCCUUUUUGUCCUUUUAUAUUUUUCUAAAGAAAACUAAGAUAUAAACUACCAAGUGCUCUUAAGAAUAAAAAUAAGAAUAAGAAUACAAAGGAGCACUACUCUUGGCUACACGAAAGAUCUUGGGAUUCAUGACACUGAGGGCAGGGAGAAGAAAGAACACCAGCCACGCAGAGAUACAAAUAAGCUCAUCAAAUGAGCAGCUGGUUUGUCUCACUCAGCCUGAAUUUGCAUUAAGUGUUCAAAAGUGAGUUUCUGGCUUGCACUAGUGUUUUGCCCUAAAUCUAAGGAUGGUGCCUAGUGGUGGCCCUGUGUUCUGAGGACAGAGAGAGCUGGAGGGGUGGAGGGAAAUGCAUCGGCACUCAUUUGGUGUAACCAAGAAGAGGGGGAAAGAUGUCUUGAUAGAAUCAAAGUUGCCAAAAACAAAGAAGAGUUUAUCAAGCAGAUUUCUAACAUUUAGUAGAAACUACUUCAUAGCUCUCAUUUUUAGGGGGUUCUAUCUAUAAUUUAUGGUAAAUAGUUGGGAGGCAAAGGGAAGAAUGUGUGUGGGGGGAUUAUUAAUUUGAAGUAUAAGCUAAAUUGUUUAUUAAAAAGCCUAUUUUGGAUGAACAAGUUUAGAGAGAUAAACUGACUAAUGUGUCCUCCAGUUUAGAAUUUCACCUUACCCGACCCAGGCACUUCUUAAAAACACAGAUCCUCAGUGCAGCUCUGCCAGCAUCAAGGCUUUUAAAAUAUGUAGUAUUUAGGCCAUUUAAACCAUACUUAUUACUCAAUAACCCAAGAAACAAUUUUGGGUUAGCCAUCUAAUAUAGCAAAUAAAAUAGAUUUUUUAAAGAAAUCCAAAAUUGUCUUAAAGGAAUGGACCCCUUGAAGAAAAAAAAAAAAAGUUUUGUUCCUCAGUUAGAAUGCUCACUAGCUCACUAGCAAGAAUUUUUAUUUUCUUGAAAGCAAUUAUAUAUAUUUUGGAAAGUUCAUGUUAUUGGAAUUGAAGUUCAAAUUAAGCAACUUCUGAGCCUAGAACUUUAAUUACUUUUUCCUAAAUGUCCCAACACUUACAUACAAAUUUCUUUGAAGACAUAACUGGACAUGGCAGACACUGCUUUGAACAAAAACCAGCCUAGUGAAUUGACUGAGUACAGUCCUUUAAGGCUGCCCAGUUCAUUCUAUUAGAUGACUAAGGAAAACUAGAAAAAGAAUACAGUUCACCCUUGUCAAGGUCAAAUGUGAAAGACAGAAGUUUAUUUAAUGUAGAGGUAAAUGAAGGUGAGCUGUUUUCAGCAUCUUAGUUUGACCAUGAAAAUGUCUAUAGAAUUAUGUGUAGUUGUUCCGUACGAUUUUAUUUUCUUCAUUUAUUUAUUUACAGUCUUAUUUAUGUUCUGUUUAAUAUAUAGUUUGAUUCUGGCCAUUUUAAAUAUUUGACACAGAAGAGACUAUAUUGGAAUAUUUACAGCUUUAUAAGUCUUUCAUCAGAUUAGCUGUUGACUUUUUGUAAUACAAAAAGUUUCAGACAAGUAUUAAAGAAUAAAAUCUGUCUCAGGCUGGUAGUUAGCAGUUGUGACCAAGAUGCUUUUGGUUGUUGUAUUUCACAAAAUUUCCUCAUUUCUAACAUGAGAGAUGAACUUAUUUUAAUAUAAUCCUUUUUCUACACUUUAAAAGUCAGCAAUAGUGUUAUGUAUUUAUAGGCAGCUUUUAAUAAUCUUGUCAUAUUUGUACUAACCCAAAUGAUUCACAGUGACAAAACAUUUUAAUAACUUGAUCACAAAACCAUAUGGACAAAUAUGAAUUUUAAUAUUAUAAAUACUAUUUUUAAAAGGUAGAAUUUAUUCGCACAGGGUAAAAAGAAUGUAAUAUUUAGUUCUCAAGUUUGAAUUAUCAGUAUAUUAUUACAAUUUUGUAUAUCAGAAUCUUAAGUGUUACAGGUACAAAAAGAAUAUUGCUAGCCAAAUGAACAAAGUUUAGCUAAAUCUCUGUAGCAUGCAAAUCAAAUAAAUUAAAAUUUUUUGCUAUUGCUUUAUCUAUAUUGUCUUAAAUAUCAAAAGCUCAGGACUGAACUUAAUAUUUAAUCAGGUUAAAUUCUGAACAUGUUUCUGUUUUAAUUUGUCUUGUUUGUAAACGUAUGCAAAUACAUCACAUAGAUUAACUGGUUUCUGCACUUUCCAUGUGUUUGUGGGUGGAAAAAAAUUCAGUGGUUUUUUUUAAAAAAAAAAGCAAAAACAAAGCUACAUAUUGCCUAAUACUCUAUUUCAGUGUCGUUUAUUGUUCAGUUUAUUUCCCUGAUUGGCACAAACACAAGAGUUUCCUUGAACCAUGUACCAAGCAAAUACAAAAUAUUUCAUGAAGAAAUCCCCAGGCUGGCAGUUUGUGAUGAAUAGUUCUUGUUGGAACUAUAUGUAUUGCUGAUAAAAAAGGACGAAGUAUUUUCAUUGAGCAAAUAAAAUGAAGGGCUCCAGAAUAUGUGCUCUGUGGUCGCUGCGCCUGGGCUGGCAGUGUGCUCCACAGAGAGGCAGCCGUCCCAGGAGGUUAUCUACCCACACACCCCAGUCCUGCCCUGCCGUGCCCCCCACAGGCUGCUCAGUGCCUGGGAAGCCAGAAACGCUGCCCGUGAAAUACAGAACACAGGAUGCAGAAGCACGUUUGUGUGGCAGAGUCUACUUGAAUCAUCCAAAACCCAAGAUCGCCCUCCUGCCUCUGACAGUAUAGAAGGCGUGACUGAAUGUGGCUGCCUUUUGAAAAAGGUUCCAUAGAGACACUGAGGUCUCUGAUUCAGAAGGAGAUGAUGUGUCUACACCUUUCACCUCUGAAGCUUCUAAAGAGCUAGUAAUUAUUUUAUAUAAUAAGACGUCAUGCAUUUUAAAUAAAUAUGCAACAAGACCUCAGGCUUAUUAUACUAGGUUAUCUUAAACACCUGAAAUAAGUAAAUGAUUUGCCAAAUGAUUCCGCUCCAUAUGAAUAAUACCUUCAAAGAUACAUAGAGAUUAAUGUUUUAUUUACCACUUCUGUGCAAUCGCUAUUUUAAAAUUGAGAAAACUCAUCCACAGUAAUGGGUGUCAUUACUAUUCAGUCUUGAUUGAUUUUGGUCUCAGACUAGAAGAUAAAAAUGGUUUACCAGUCUUGGAAAGAAACUAUAGUUUAAUAGCCACAGGAAAAGAUGCAUUUUCAAAAAUCAAAAGCACAGUGAGAUGACUAGAGCGGGACAUCCUACCAAAUCCAGUGUUGAGCAAGCGUCUCCUGAACAGCAGACGCUUGUCCUUUCUGGCUUAGUGUUUCAGGUUGGUGUUUCUCGUCUCCAGUUCUUGAUGAUGAUCUUGUGUUUGUGCCACUGCGUAGUGGCCCGAAGCUAGGGGAGCGUGGCUGGAGCAGGCUGCACAGUGGAGCAGACACCCUCCUAGCAGAAGAGAAAGUCCAGCAAACCAGCCCAGAAACAGGGCCUCCCCAAACUCCCACCUGGGGACAAAGUCUGGGACGUUCUCAUCCCAGAACUCCUGAACCGUCUUGUGGGCAACCCAAGAGACGGGAACCAGGGCUGUGACUCCCGAGGCCCAGGACAGAAUUCCUCCCAGGAUCAGCAGUCGCCUCUUGAGAUCUCUCUGACUCUCUCCAAUUCUCAAACAGUCCAGGCCAAACCCAGAGACCAGCAGGCCCAGAAAUCCCAGCCCAUUUGACAGAAACAUUAAGAUCCUGGAGACCCUGAGUUCAGCAGGCAAAGCCAGGAAGGAGUCAAAGUCCUUGCAUUGCAUCCCCACUUCCUCUUGGAUGACACAGGUUUGCCAGAGUCCCAUGGUCCAGUUUUCCAUUUCAUUUAAGUCCAGGUUGAGGUUCUUCCAGUGUGGCAGGUAGUUUGUAAGACAGGAUAAAACCCAUCCCAGCAAAGAUAAUGAAACUCCAGCUAGUUGAGCUACAGUUCUAAAUACUAAAGCCAUUAUAAUGUCCUGAGAGCUUUAGCCAAACUAACUCCUGCCCUUCGGUUGCUGUGAAAAGAAGUGUGACACUUGUGUUAUAACUUAUGAAACUCAGAAAUAUUUCUUCAUUGUGUAUAUAGGAGGAUUCUUGCCAGAGUUGCUAUUGUUUGAUUCCAUGUUGAAUGGGUUUCACAAAAGGAUAGGGAAAUAAUGCCGCCAACCAGUAAUGCCAAGGUGUGGCCAAGAUUGUGUUUGUGUCCUGUGGGCUGGAUUUGACAGAAAGCAGUUUGUCACUGAAAUAUAAUUAAGUGAUAAUCUCCUUUCAUUGUCAAGGUUAAAAUGGCUUUCAUGUUAUUCCCAACCUUUCUAACAAAGAAUUAAGUCUAAAUGCAAAAUGUUUAACUGAUGGUUUUGGUUCAACUCCUCCUGCUUUGUGUUUCACUAACUGCACCUGUCAGAUUUUCAUCUCUUAUAGUUCUCACAUUUCAAAUGUGCAUGUUAUGGUAAUACUGAGUGUUAUUUUUUAAAAAUAGGUUUAAGAAAAGUAUUUCUUAACCAAAUAAAUCAAUCUUAUCAGAAA